AGUGAAACCGGCGGCCCUGGCACGUGACCUAGGACCGGCUCACCGGGUCGCUUGGUGGCUCCGUCUGUCUGUCCGUCCGCCCGCGGGUGCCAUCAUGGCGGACGCGGCCAGUCAGGUGCUCCUGGGCUCCGGUCUCACCAUCCUGUCCCAGCCGCUCAUGUACGUGAAAGUGCUCAUCCAGGUGGGAUAUGAGCCUCUUCCUCCAACAAUAGGACGAAAUAUUUUUGGGCGGCAAGUGUGUCAGCUUCCUGGUCUCUUUAGUUAUGCUCAGCACAUUGCCAGUAUCGAUGGGAGGCGCGGGUUGUUCACAGGCUUAACUCCAAGACUGUGUUCGGGAGUCCUUGGAACUGUGGUCCAUGGUAAAGUUUUACAGCAUUACCAGGAGAGUGACAAGGGUGAGGAGUUAGGACCUGGAAAUGUACAGAAAGAAGUCUCAUCUUCCUUUGACCACGUUAUCAAGGAGACAACUCGAGAGAUGAUCGCUCGUUCUGCUGCUACCCUCAUCACACAUCCCUUCCAUGUGAUCACUCUGAGAUCUAUGGUACAGUUCAUUGGCAGAGAAUCCAAGUACUGUGGACUUUGUGAUUCCAUAAUAACCAUCUAUCGGGAAGAGGGCAUUCUAGGAUUUUUCGCGGGUCUUGUUCCUCGCCUUCUAGGUGACAUCCUUUCUUUGUGGCUGUGUAACUCACUGGCCUACCUCGUCAAUACCUAUGCACUGGACAGUGGGGUUUCUACCAUGAAUGAAAUGAAGAGUUAUUCUCAAGCUGUCACAGGAUUUUUUGCGAGUAUGUUGACCUAUCCCUUUGUGCUUGUCUCCAAUCUUAUGGCUGUCAACAACUGUGGUCUUGCUGGUGGAUGCCCUCCUUACUCCCCAAUAUAUACGUCUUGGAUAGACUGUUGGUGCAUGCUACAAAAAGAGGAAAAGCACUUCCAGACUGGGAAGAGUUCAGCAAAACAGGGGUUAGAGGACAUUAAACCCCAAAUAGAAGAAAAGAUAAGAGAAAACCUAACCACCUAGCCAUUCAAAAUGAGCUGCAAAUCCCAAGGUGAUGACAGACCUUUGCAGAUAAGAUCCAGGGACCUUUGCCAAUGUGGCUAUGAAAGCUGCGGCGAAAAGGACAGGGGCCACAGUCCUGGACAGCUGCAAAUACCCUGACAAAAAAGAAGAAAAGGGAGAUCCUGGGCACAUUUCCCUCAAAAUCUAUUCUAGAAUAUAACAUUAAACCAUGGAUUUGAGAACACCUUGCUUGAGAACACCUAGAAAAAUAAGUGGUAUCUUCACAAAGAACAAGAUGCGGCGAAAAUGAUAAAAAUAUCAACAAUAAUUUGUUACUUAUUUACUCAGAAGGCCACUAGGAAAAUUCCUUGGGCCAUACAUAGUGUUCCUUGUUUCCAGUUAGACAUUGAUUGUCUCACGAUUGAAGAGGCUAGUAGGAAAAUAUCGAUCUCAGAGACUGCCCAGUCAGGUGGAUUCAUGUAACUGCUGUGCUCCUUCACCCCAGUUGGUUAUCCGAUUGCUGCAGAGCUUGCUGAGGAAGUAUCUCUAGUUCUGUGCUCCUAGACCCUGGUCAGCCUAGUAGUGGUCAGUGCCCACUACACUUGCCAAAUUUGCAGAAGGCACCACUGUUGGGAUGAAAAGCUAAUAUUUCAAAGUCAAGAUUCUAAAAUAACUUGAAACAGUGGGCUGAAACCAGCAGGAUGAAAUUUAAAAGAGUAAGUGGAGAGACCUGCAUUUAGAUUAAAAAAAAAAAAUCAGCUGCAUAAGCAUAGGAUAUAGGAAGUUUGGUUUGCCAGAGGUGCCUGAGAAAAAGGCUAAGGGCUUGCAGCUGAUCUCAGGUUGAAUAGAAACCGGUAGGAAUGGAGCAGCUGCUUAAAAAGAUAGUGGCUCUCCCCACCUCUUGUUAUUUUAGUUACAAAGGGGUGAAACAGUGAAAAAUAUGGGAGACAGCCGGGCACGGUGGCUCACACCUGUAAUCCCAACACUUUGGGAGGCCGAGGCGGGCGGAUCACGAGGUCAGAUCUAGACCAUCCUGGCUAACCCGGUAAAACUCUGUCUCUACUAAAAAUACAAAAAAAUUAGCCAGGCGUGGUGGCAGGCGCCUGUAGUCCCAGCUACUCGGGAGGCUGAGGCAGGAGAAUGGCGUGAACCUGGGAGGCGGAGCUUGCAGUGAGCCAAGAUCUCGCCACUGCACUCCAGCCUGGGAGAUAGAGCAAGACUCCGUCUCAAAAAAAAACAAAAAAAACAAAAAAGAAAAAUAUGGGAGACAUAUUAACAGCAACUGCUGUUAAUGGUUUCUAAUAGAUCCCCUCAGAGGUAUUCAUUCCAAGUACACAUAAGCAAAUGCAUGCUUUUUAUUUUUUCACAUAAAUGGUGGUAUGUUGUGCACCUUGUUUUUUAUUUCACUUAACUAACAGCAUUUCUUAGCGAUUAUUUCAUCAGUAUACAAAAUGAUUCCUCAUUCUUUUGUAGGGAUGCAUCGUAUUCUACUGUAUAUAUGUAUCAUAAUUUAUUGGUCCUUUUGCCGGACAUGUAGAUUAUUUCCAGUAUUUUGCUAUUACAAACAAUGCUGCAAUAAAUAACACGUCAUUGCUAUUACAAACUGUUUGCUAUUACAAGCCAUGCUAAAAUGAAUAAGAUGUAAUUCCCAACAAGUGGGCAUGUAUCUGAAAAACAUCUCUUCAAGAAGUAAAAUCACUGACUUAAAGGGCAUGCACAUUUUUAAACUUGGUAGAUACUGUCCAAUUGUGUCAUUUUACCCUCCUACUAAAAAUGUAUGAAUGUCUGUUUCUCUACAUCUCACCAAUAGAAUGUAUAAUAAACCUCAUUGAUCUUUGACAGUUUGAGAGGUAAAAAUAAUAACAAUA